GGGCACCGCGGGGCAGCGGCGCCGCAGCCUGGGCUGGCGGAACCUCGCGCUCCGACUCGCCCCCCGCCUGUAGCUCGGUCGGCGUUGCGGGCAGGCGCCGCUCCGCUGGGGAUUGCUAUGCUAUGCCUUGUAUGACUAAGACCUCUUACCAAGAAUACGUGUCAGACCAUAAAACCACUGCCAAGGAGUGCGGGGGUGGCAAUGAAACAGCCCAACAGGAAAAGGAAGCUUAAUAUGGAUUCCAAAGAGCGUUUGGAUCAGGACGGACGCUUGGAGCAAGCUGAAGAGGAAAAGAAGCCCAAGGAUAGCACAACCCCUUUGAGUCACGUCCCUUCAGCGGCUGCACAGGGAGCAUGGUCUUGGGAGUGGUACUUGAAAGAACAGAAGGCUGUCGCAGCACCUGUUGAGCUGUUUUCCAAGGAUCAGUCCUUUCCAGAGCAUGAAAAUGGUUUUCAGAUUGGAAUGAGAUUAGAAGGCAUUGAUCCCCGACAUCCAUCGGUAUUCUGUGUGCUUUCUGUAGCGGAGGUUUGUGGUUACCGUCUAAGACUUCAUUUUGAUGGUUAUUUAAGUUGCUAUGAUUUUUGGACCAAUGCUGGUUCCCCUGACAUUCAUCCAGUAGGAUGGUGUGAAAAGACCAAACAUGAACUGCACAUCCCUAAGGGUUAUAGAAAAGAUAAAUUUGUUUGGAUGGAUUACUUGAAGGCCUGCAAAUUGCAAAAUGCUCCAAAGAAAUUAUUCAGAAACAGAAGUCCUAAUGGGCCAAUGUCUAAAGAAUUUCAGGUUGGAAUGAAGCUGGAGGCCGUGGACAGGAAGAACCCUUCCUUGGUGUGUGUGGCGACCAUAGCAGAUAUUGUUGAAGAUCGCUUACUAGUGCAUUUUGACAACUGGGAUGAUAGUUACGAUUACUGGUGCGAUGUUAAUAGCCCUUAUGUCCAGCCAGUUGGUUGGUGUCAGGAGAAUGGAAGAACUCUGAUAGCACCCCAAGGUUAUCCCAAUCCAGAAAAUUUUUCCUGGACAGAAUACCUGGAAGCUACUCAAACCAAUGCAGUUCCUGCCAAAGUUUUUAAAAUGAGGUUGCCUCAUGGUUUUCUGCCAAAUAUGAAACUUGAAGUUGUGGAUAAACGGAACCCCAGGUUAAUUCGUGUUGCUACGAUUGUAGAUGUUGAUGACCAAAGAGUAAAGGUUCAUUUUGAUGGUUGGGACCAUAAGUAUGACUACUGGGUGGAGGCAGACAGCCCUGAUAUCCACCCGAUCGGAUGGUGUGAUGUCACAGGGCAUCCACUGGAAGUGCCACAGCGAACGAAUGACCUGAAGAUCCUUCCAGGUCAAGCUGUCUGUCCUACUCCCGGGUGCCGAGGAAUAGGCCAUAUCCGUGGUCCACGUUAUUCGGGACAUCACAGUGCUUUUGGCUGCCCGUAUUCAGACAUGAACUUGAAAAAGGAGGCAACACUUCACGAUCGUUUGAGAGAACAAACACAGGCAAAUUUGGAAUCAGACUCUUCACAUUCAAAAUCAAAAAGCCUCUGUAGUUUGAACUUCAAUGGAAAACAUGAAAAGGUGAACAGUCAGCCCAGACUUGUACAGCAGGCAAAGUGUUUGAAAAUCAAAGGAAAAGAAGAUAUUGACUUGGAUAAUCUCUUCAGAGGUACAAGGCUUGAGGGAGUGACAACUCUGAACACCACAUUCCACAGCAACAAGUCUGGUGCAUGUGGGCAGCCACGCCAGAGGCUUCCUUGGAGUAUUCCAGAAAUAACCCUCUCGAACUGGAGUCUGUCUCUGACACAUCCUCUUCUCCAUACUGACACUGUCUCUGGUUAUAAUAGAAUGCAGCUUCACCUUUCCACAUCACUCCAGACUAGAUGCGUAAUCAGUCCCUCUGACACUGCUGCUGGAAUAGUAAUCUGACACCUGCCGUCAGCUGAGGGUCCUUGGCUAUUGACUGUGCAGAGCUGUGGGAGAGUGGACAGCCCAGAGACAACCGGAGAAGCAGAUCUUAUUACUGGAAUAAUUGCACCUUUGUGUUCCAACACUGCACAGUAUUUUUCUCAGGAGCCAAAACUGGCUUCUAAGAUUCUUGGAUUCCAGGCUCACCAUUCCAGGCAAGGUGAUAGGGAAUUGUAAUAACUUCACCUUAUUCCCGGUAUCAGAUUAACAUGCAUGUUGGCUUUGAAAGAUGUGGCAUUUCCAUCCUUAGAGUCUAUGAACAUGUACGGAUUAUUUAUGGGUGUAGAGGAUGCCCCCCAAAGUAAAGCAGUUCUCUCCUUUAUUCAUCAUUCCUCCCACAGCACUGCCAGGCUUUGUCUUCUUUGUCUCUAAUUGCAGUGCUAAAGGGAAAUGUCCCCAGGCCAGAGCAAAGAACCUUUACCUUCAAAUAUACCUUGGAUCAAAGAGAGAAAGCCCCUGCAUCCCUCCAUCAGAUUGAUAGUGUGAGACACUUUUUCUCUUGAUUAUGGGUACCGUGGACUUGAAAAAAAACAACAAAAACAAACAAAAACUUCCCUGAUUCAUAGUCUCCUUGGGGAGACAGGCCUGUUUUGUACGAAAAAGUUUUCUAAACCUGAGAUUUAUACUCCAUAAAGACACAGACAAUGAGGAACAAUUCAAGGCUUGUUCUAAAGGAUGCAGCAAAAGUGUUAGGUAGAAGGUUCAGGGUACUGGAGCAAUGUAGAGAAUGAGGCCGUGGAAUUCCUUUUCUUAAAAACCUUCAGACAAAGAUUGCCCUGGGAUUCUCUACCCAGACAGCACUGCUAUUUUGACAUUUCAUUAAAUUUCUAAGAGAUAAAACUUAUAAAUAGUAAUGCCAAGCACCUUAUGUCUAAGGAGAAGAAUCAGGAUUUGAUGUCUUGAUUCCCACACGUAUCAUUGGACAAUCUGUUUCAGUUCAACUGAAAUUCAUUACUGAGAACUAGAAAAUGAGAGUUGUUGCUGGUUCCAGCAUACUUGAGUUAAGUCAUGUUGAUUAUUACAAAAGUUAAGACACAAGAAAUUUUUAUCUCUUUAUAAAUUAAAGGAAUAGCUAUUAUGAGCAAUUUUAGAUAAGGAAGGGGCAUAAAAUAUUUCAAUACCAUAUGAAAAUAGGCUUAGGAACUAUACCUGAUAUAUGUUAAGUAUUUGGUUGAGUCACUCUGAGUACACUGCUUGUCUUGUUGCUAUGGUUACUGCUGCCUUGUGGGGGUACACCGUGUAUCAUUUUUGUCAUGGACUUUAUUUAUUAGCACAGACAACUCUUUCUUCUAUUAUUUACGUGGUUCUCCCUCGUUCAUUAUUUUUUAAUGUUUUUCAUUGUUGAUUUGUUUUCUUUUUUUGAAUACUUUUUAGUUGAUGCAUUUUUUUCUUCACAUUUUGACUGCCAAGUUUUCAGUGAUUUUGAGGUUCAGAAAAAGUCAGAUUAUAAAAUAAUCACAAAAAAAUUAAUAAAGUAAACAAGAAGUAUUUAAAGAAAGUAGAAACUAAACAGAGAGAGAAGUUUCCUGAGUUUUUUAGAUAUAGGUAUUUUGAUGACAUUUUUCUCUUUUAUUUGCCUUUAGAAAGAGAUAAUUAAAAAAUAAAAACCAAUUUUCCCCAGUGGUGAUAGAUUGUUAUACACUCUUGCCUAGUUUUUAUUCUGUUAUUAUGAAAAACAUACUUUUGGCCAGGCGCAAUGGCCCAUGCCUGUAAUCCUAGCACUUUGGGAGCCCAAGGCAGGCAGAUCACGAUCACCUUAGGUCAGGAGUUUGAGACCAGCCUGGCCAACGUGGCAAAAACCCAUCUCUACUAAAAAUACAAAAAUUAGCUGGGCGUGGUGGCAUGCCUGUAAUCCCAGAUACUCGAGAGGCUGAGGCAGGAGAAUCGCUUGAGCCUGGGAGGCAGAGGUUGCAGUGAACCAAUAUUGUGCCACUGCACUCCAGCCUGGAUGAGAGAGCGAGAUUCCAUCUUAAAAAAAAAAAGAAAAAGAAAGAAAGAAAGAAAAGAAAAAUUAGCAGUGGCAUCAAAUAACUGUUUUCUUAAUAUGUUCACUAUGAUAGUAAUACUGAUAAUAACAAUAUGUUCAUCUAGCAGUUUUCAUUUAUAAAUUACUUUCAUGUCUGUCCCAUUUUUCCUCUGAAAGAUUGUGGUUUCUGUUUUACUGUUGAGGCACUUGAUCUGCAGAGCAGGUGAUUUACCCAACGUCACACAGCUCAAUAAUGACAGAGUUGCAGCUUAGAGUGACCUCUGCAAAUCCAGAGCUUUUCCCCCAUGGCCUACCAUUUCAUCAGGACACCCACGGAGUUAACUGACUGUGUGGUUUCACGGAAAGUGCCAUUAGAAGUGGGGUUGGAGACCUGACUUUAAGCCCAGCCACAAACUCGCUUUGUGGCUGAGCCCUGGGGGUGGGCCUGAGUCUCCUUGCCUGUCGCAUAGAGAGCCUUUCUCUACCUCUCAAAGCAGCUGAGUGCAUAAGAAAGGGCAUUAAAAAUAAGGCACACUAUAUAUAAAGGUCUGACCAGCACUCAGACAUUUCUCCAUAAAUUCAUUGGAAGUAGGCUAAUAACACUUCAGAGGGAGCCUCCUGCCCAGUGCCUCCUGCCUAGCAGGGGCCCAUGUGGUGUGUGUGCUCAGGAUGCAGUGACUUUUGCUUCCUGUCUGACUACUGCUGAGUUCUUGCUCAAACACAAAAGCAAACUUCUGCUGAAACUUUGAGAAUUUUGCUUUGUGCUGAAUAGAUUGGCGCUGAAGUCCGAAGGCAAAAGCCAUUUCAGUGUCUCUGACAUGCUUGUUUGUUUAAUGACAGUCUCUUUUUUCUUAAGAAGAAUGCCUUUCUGCUUGGCCAGAAAUUUCUUCUUGGAAAUGACAGAAUCGCUGUCUCACUGUUAAUGAAUUUUACAGCCCAGAUUCCUUUUAGUUUAAUGAAAUAUGGACAUAUCAACCCAAAUCCAUGCUUUAAAACAAAGUAGAGGAAACUACCACUCCCCCCGAAACACUGAGGCGUUUUCCGCCUGGCUGACCAGUGCAACUCUGAGGUCAUCGCCUUAUAGCCACUUGCAUAGUGAUUAGAUUAUGGUUCACAGUUGAUAUUAGUAUGCUUUAAAAAUAAACACAAAGUCCCUUAUACAGAGAAGAGGCUGAGGACAAAAGCUUAGUCAUCUGUGAUUCACAUACAUAUCAUGAAGUAUAAUAGUGGAAGGAUCCUUCCCUGGGGGUCUGAGAAUCUGGGUUCCAACUCAGUCACUGUUUCUCUGGCACUGGGCACCCCUCCCCCGGACCACUGUGAGAUGAUGCUUUGUGCUUGGCUAAAUUGCAGAGGUUUUUAAUUGUUUCCUUAUUAUAUUUUGUAUCAAAAGAUGGUUUUUAAAAUCACUUCUGUUAACAUGAGGGUUGGAGAAUAACAAGUUUUCAAAGUUGUAACUCUUGUUUGAGCAUUGUUUUCUAUUUAGCCUUAAUAUAAAAAACCUUUGCUGACCAAGCUGUCUAGAUUGCCCCAGCAAAAAAAUCAAUCAGUCAAUCAAUCAAUCAAUCUGUGCCUUUAACAUACUAUCGAAGAAAACUUACUUUCAAAUAUAUCUGGUCAGGUGAAUGGUUCUUCCUCUUAACGGUUGGGGCAUAGAACCCUACACCUCUAUCCCAGCCUUGACAACUUUUAAGCCUAGUGAUUUGAAAGAUAAUGAGGUCUGAGCAAAGUGAACAUGGUCAUAAUAUCAGAUGUCAUUAACAAUAUAAAUUAAUCAGAGAAUGAAUGUCCAAAAUGUCAGAAAUUUUCUUUGGGGGGCUUCAUUGUGCCAAAGGUUAAAAUAUCUUUAAACAUCAUGAACAUCUAGGAAAUUCAUAAGAGAAGUUGGGAUGACUAAAAUGGUUUCUCUUUCAUAUGUAACUCAGGAUGAUAUAACUAGUCACUGAAAAUAGGCAUGAGAUGAAAUUUGACUUGCUUCUCCAAAUGGACAGCGCUAAGGUAUCUAGUCAUACUGUCUCACAGAUUCCUGAGGUUAAAGGUGCAAUUCCUCUGAACGAGGCUUAAAACCAGGUGUUUUCAACUGUAUUUUAGUGUCUUCCAGUGGAUUCAUGUGGAAUAACCUGUAAGUGAAGCAGAGGGAAGCUGAGCUUCAGGGAAAGGGAAAAAGAGCCCGAAGCCCAGUUGUGUGGUGCCACCUCCCUGGCCAUGCAGGGGCCUUGCGGCAUUUCCACAGAACCAUGUCUGUGGUCCCAGCAUCAUUCAUGGGUUCAUCCAGGACAUAUUCUUUACAUACCCAGCAUUAUUCUAGGCACAGGCCAUACCACAGUAAAUAAGAGCAGCGCUGGUCUGAGCUGUUGUGGAGCUCUGUGGCGAAGCGUUAAUCUGUUUGAGGUUACAGCUGAGAUAAGUGCCAGGCAAGGGCAGCACAGGGCUGGGAGAUCAGGGCCUGUCUCUGGGAAAGUGACAUGGCCCAGAUCCAAAGGAUGAGGGGAAUGAAGUGUCAGGGAAGGGGCGGGGGCGAGGGCAGAGGGCCUCGGAGGAAAAGAAGGAUGUUUGCUAAGUGGUUCCAUUCACUGGCAGUAAGAGUACUGAGUGUGGUAAACCCCUGGAGGGAGUAUCUGAUUUGAUAUUCUCACAGAGAGAGGAAACUAAGGUACAGGAAUUGACUUUCAUACCCCUGACUCCACACCUCAGGGAUGGAGCCAGGGACUGAAUCCAGGUCUUACUACAGAGCCUGUACUGGACUGCCAUCCUGCACUGCCUCCUAAUGCGAGCCGGUGGGCACUCUGGGGGACUUAAGUGACAGCAAUGUAUGAGACAAUCUGUUUGCCAAGAAAAAAAAAUUGUGACGAUGCAGGCUGAGUCAGGUGUCUCAGUCCAUCAGUUUCGCAUACUAAGAUCUACAGUGCUGUAAAGAUGGAGUUUAGAGAGUCUUUAGUGGGGAAGAUGUUAUCACUAAGAAUGGACAAACACACAAAAGCAUUGAGAGCCUCUAUCUCCCAGGUAGGAAAGAAGCAGAGGGACUUGAAGAGCAACAUCAGAAGAGAGGUGUUGUGUUUGCUAGCACCUGGCAAAAACAGGCAAAAAAUGUCUUUUAUACAUUCUGAAGUAUAGAACUUAACCUAAGCAUGUCAAUUAGACUUUGCAAAAGCAUUUGCACGCCAUGAUUUUUUUCAGUCACUUUUCACAUAUUUAGGUCAUCUGCCUUUAUUGAACAUAUCAUUUAUGUGCCCACUAGACUGUGAACUUCCCAUCAACUUAAAAUAACAACAGAGGGAGACAAGCUCUCCAAAGAAAGAGUUUACUGGGGAAUAGCAAGAAAUUGUCAUUAGGAUACGCAUGCUGCAGUGGACCAUAGGCGCAACCAGAGAAGCAAAGGAAGGCAAGGUUUUUAAAGGGGAAAGGAGGGCAGUUGCAUUCGUUGUUUUGAAGCAACUAUCCUUGGCUACAAGUAUUAAUAACAAGGGUGAGUCAGUCUAUUAGUGAACAGGCCAUUAAUGAGCAGGCAUCCUCACAGAAGUAAUCUUUGUGCAAGGUUGCGAUGGCCUUUGUGAAGGUUGUGGUGUUGGCAGCCUUUUGUGAUAGUACCAGUUAUCAGACAAAUGUGCAUGAGGGCCUUCCCUUCAUGGCCUCCUGUAUCCAUUUCGUUAGGAUUGGACAUAAGUGACUCCAUUUUGGUACCAGCAACUUUCACAUUCUUAUAAGCAGGAAAUCUUCACUUAUUUUCGCAUCCUCUUAGUCUAACCCAGUUCCAGUCCUGCAGUGGAAACUCAGUACUGAGUGAAUUUUGUAGCAUUUCUGAAAAUAAGUCCCUUGCCUCUUUCUCUAUGUUUAUUGCCAUCACAAAUUAGUAUUUUAGCUAUGCAAGCAGAUGCUUUACUAACACACCUAACUAGAUUAGAAAUUAUUUUACUGUCUUAGCAUAGUGUAUUGUGAAGAGCCAACACUAGCUGGAAAUGCAUGACACUCCUUCUACCAUUUAAAAAUAGAAAGACACAAUGAACAAGGACUGGUUGAUAAUCAACGUUUGUUUAUUGGACUUGUUCUUCCGAAUGAUAAAUUUGUUCUGGGAAAUACAAAUUAACGGGACGUCCUGCUGGAAUCCUCUGAAUUGUGAAUGUUUCUGCCUUGCCAACAAGUGUGCACUGUAGUUUAGGGAUUUACAGCACUCCAUUUGUAUAGCACGAUUUCGUCCACUGCAGUACAUUUUCCAUUUUGUUGGCCUGUUCUUUCCCUGAGAACUAGCAGUGUUGGAAUUCUUUAUGUCCAUUAGCCUACUAACGCACUGAGUCUUGAAACAGAAAAUUCUCCACUAUUGGCAAAGUAAGAAAAAGUGAGCCAUUUGCAAAACGUAAAUUCAGAUUCUCUUUCUUUCCUCAGAAGAUUAGAUGGAAAAAUACAUAAGAAUUGUGUAACUUGCCCUUUCAGCUGCAAAGGGCAAACAAGGAUAUUUGACCUUUAUUUUCAUUUGCUUAAAUGUUUGAAGACUGAUAUUUGUUAUUCCACAAGAGGCGUAGAAGUGCAGUAAGCCCCACUGUUCACUGUAGCCAGCAACUGGCAGGGAGUAAGUACUGAUUCAUAGUUAUUACAAUCCAAUAUAUUUCUUUAUUAAAAGUUAGCUAUAUAUAAACUGCCAUAUUCUGAAAAUGUGUAAUUAAUUUGAUACUGAAAAAUGCUGAACAUAUUUGUAUUGCUUUGUGAUUCAGAAAGCACUCUGUAGACUUAACUUCAGAGCCAUUGUUUUAACAUCACUUUAAAUUGUAUUUAUCCAUGCGACCAUGCCAGUUAAUAGGAAUUUCCAGUUGGUAGCAUGCUAUCAGUAGCUAUGUAUAUUCAUAAUUUAAAAAUCAAAACAUCAAAGAGAAAAUGCUUAUGAAGUCGACUUAAAGGAAAUUUUUAGUCAUUACUAAAUAUUUCUCUAAGUUCUUACAAAGCCUUUGGAGCUGCCUCCAGUUGCUUUUCAAAAAACCCAUUUCUAAAGUAGAAAUGUUCUCACUGAACAAUUGGUAUUAGGGAAACUGCAAGGGAAACACCUCAGAGCUCAAUAGCCAAAGACGCACCAUCAAUGUUGAAUGAGACAGAGUCUCUACUGAUGGGAAAUUCUACAAGACUCCUCUGGUGUUUUCUGUGAUAUCUGUUCCAGCCCCACAGUGGCCACUUUCAGUUCUCCCCCACUAUUAACACUCAUCCUGCCAAGCCAAGAAUUCUUAAGGUAGUGUAGUGAACGCCAUGCUGAAAAAUAGGCUCUUACGGUGCCGGGGUCCGUGAACACAGCUCACCACUCCGAGGAGGAAACCUUCCCUUAGCACAGGCACCACCUCCUCAGACAGUCCCACAAAUACAGGAAGGUGGUGGCUCCACCCAGGGCCACAGUCAUUGUCUCCACCACAGUCACAGAACACGCCCAAUCCACUGCCGACAUUUUGAAGAAAGGGCCGCAAUCAUCCACUGAAUCUGUCCUACCAAGGAAAGCAAAUCAAGCUUGCUGCCCUAUUCGUUUCUUCCUUUUUUUUUUUUUGAGACAGAGCCUUGCUGCGCCGCCCAGGCUGGAAUGCAAUGGCAUGAUCUCAGCUCACUGCAACCUCCGCCCCGCAAGUUCAAGCGAUUCUCCUGCCUCAGCCUCCUGAGUAGCUGGGAUUACAGGCAUGCGCCAUCAUGCCUGGCUAGUUUUUGUAUUUUUAGUAGAGACGGGGUUUCACCAUGUUGGCCAGGCUGGUCUCGAACUCCUGACCUCGGGUGAUCCAUCCACCACAGCCUCCGAAAGUGCUGGGAUUACAGGCGUGAGCCACUGCGCCCGGCCUGCUGCCUUAUUCUUGAAUGGAGAUAUUCAUGCAGACUGUCAUGACCUCAGCGGCAUCUCAUUGCCCCAGAGUCGGCAGAAUUUUAGUCAGGAUCCUUCUGGACUGGCAACCAAAUUAGCUUGGUGCUCUGUGUUCUGUUGACUAGCAUACACUAAAGACACAGUGUGGAAUACUAGCAAAAGGAGUUCUGCGGGAUGUGCCUCCCUCAGGCUGAGAAGGUGUCCAUGCAUCAACAUCACAGGCUCUUGCAGCCUAGCACUGACCUGGCGGCAGCUGCCACCAGCACCUCUCACAUCGGCUUCCCCAGAGACCUGAGGCCAGAGAAAAACAGGAUCACAAACUGUGUUGAUAUCACAUGUCCAGAAUUCUUCAAUAUGUAGCACAUUAAGAACAGAUCAAUACACAUUCUACAACAAAAUUUGCUUCUUAUUCUAUUUUUCCCAUUAUGAGCUGGGAGGAAUAAAAAAUUCCCCCCCUUAGCUUUGUCUCCCUCUCUCCAGAACUCAUUUCAGACCCAUGCUAUUUCCCUAAGAGAAGAAGAGAAAAAAUUUCAUUAAAAAACGGAAGUCAUACACUUCACAGCAGCAGCCCAUGGAGCUACUGAAUUUUAUUCAAAUAGAAAAUAUGAGAGCACACUGGCAUCAGAUUAUAUUUGCAUUUUGGAAAAUAUUAGGCAUUGAUUUUGUUGAGUUGCCCUAAGCUAUAUACUUUAGAAAUUAUUGUGCACAGGUAAUAAUAGAGGGUAUAACCAUUUAUAAAGACUAUGGAACUUUGCUCUUAAAUUGUAAAAAUUACACAGUGAAUUUAUUAAUAUUUUUAUCAUUAUAAAGUCUACAAGGUUAAUUGCUUUUCAGAAUGGUGAAUGUAACUAGUUUUUACAGUUUCUAUUCAAAGGAAAAUGCUAAAGCUAAAUCAGCCAGGAUUUUAUAUGGUCCUAAAGCGUUUCCCUGACAUCGUGUGGGAGAGUAUGAGGGGAGAACAGGAUUUGGUGAGAAGUCAGAUUACGCAAGUUCUUUAUCCAGAGGAAAGGGAUACAGAUAAUUAACUUUGCAUCCAUCUUUUGACCCAGUACCCUCCCAUGUCGCAUUGUCACUAUGUCACUUUAUAAUUUUUUUAAAAAAAGUUUGGCCUCUUAUUAUGCCCAAUUGAGUAGCAUGAGUAUUGUGGGUAAUUUCUUACUUAUAAUACUCAGUAUCCUGUAUUUACUGCCUUCCUGAACUCUCACCUAUGUUUUGCGAUAGAAUUUUGCUAGCUCACAUCCUGAUCAGUUAAAAAUUUGUAUUAACAAAUAAAGAACAUGAGAGAAUUGCA